CAGCCUCCGCUAGGGGACCCCCUCCAUGGCUUCCCACCGGGUUGUUCCAGGCCUCAGCUUCGCCGAAAGGCCUCACCACCUCCGACCUCCGCCUGCUCUGGGGAUGCUCCCAGCCCUGCUGCGGCAGAACGCGACAUGCUAACCGGAAUCCCUAGGCCGCCUGUCUCCUACCCAUACUUAGAGGCCCCGCUCAGACGGUCCUUAAAACGUCUGAAAGGCCGUUCCUGCCAGAGUCCCUGCUACCUGUUACCUCCACCCCUAUUUAGUCCUAGUGGACAGCCUCGCUCACCUUCCCUGGGAUGACACUUCUGGCGGCUGAGAUGAGCGAGCCUCUCUGGGCUCUGCCGCCGGGUGUGGGCUGACCUGCCUACAGCUGGGGCCUGAUAAGGCAGCAGCAAAAGGGUGGAGGGGAGGCAGUGUUGAAGCUGGGGCAAGUAAUUUUCCCCAAUUUACAGGGAAAAACCGAAAUUCAGAAAAGUUUAAUGUCACCCAGGGGCUGGAGCCCAGACCUCUGGCAGCUCUCACUUUCACAAUGCCCUUGGGCUGACUAGGCUGCAGAGGGGUUUCACCCCAACCCCAGGGCACCUCAAGUGUCCCCACCAAACCUUCCUAACACCUGUCCACUAAGCUGUACUAGGCCCUUGCAACUGACCUAUGGGACCUGAGGCCUGGCCCCUCAUGGCUCCUGUCACCAGGUCUCAGGUCAGGGUCCAGCAGGCCCUGAGCUGACGUGUGGAGCCAGAGCCACCCAAUCCCGUAGGGACAGGUUUCACAACUUCCCGGAUGGGGCUGUGGUGGGUCACAGUGCAGCCUCCAGCCAGAAGGAUGGGGUGGCUCCCACUCCUGCUGCUUCUGACUCAAUGCUUAGGGGUCCCUGGGCAGCGCUCGCCAUUGAAUGACUUCCAAGUGCUCCGGGGCACAGAGCUACAGCACCUGCUACAUGCGGUGGUGCCCGGGCCUUGGCAGGAGGAUGUGGCAGAUGCUGAAGAGUGUGCUGGUCGCUGUGGGCCCUUAAUGGACUGCCGGGCCUUCCACUACAACGUGAGCAGCCAUGGUUGCCAACUGCUGCCAUGGACUCAACACUCGCCCCACACGAGGCUGCGGCGUUCUGGGCGCUGUGACCUCUUCCAGAAGAAAGACUACGUACGGACCUGCAUCAUGAACAAUGGGGUUGGGUACCGGGGCACCAUGGCCACGACCGUGGGUGGCCUGCCCUGCCAGGCUUGGAGCCACAAGUUCCCAAAUGAUCACAAGUACACGCCCACUCUCCGGAAUGGCCUGGAAGAGAACUUCUGCCGUAACCCUGAUGGCGACCCCGGAGGUCCUUGGUGCUACACAACAGACCCUGCUGUGCGCUUCCAGAGCUGCGGCAUCAAAUCCUGCCGGGAGGCCGCGUGUGUCUGGUGCAAUGGCGAGGAAUACCGCGGCGCGGUAGACCGCACGGAGUCAGGGCGCGAGUGCCAGCGCUGGGAUCUUCAGCACCCGCACCAGCACCCCUUCGAGCCGGGUUCCUCGACCAAGGUCUGGACGACAACUAUUGCCGGAAUCCUGACGGCUCCGAGCGGCCAUGGUGCUACACUACGGAUCCGCAGAUCGAGCGAGAGUUCUGUGACCUCCCCCGCUGCGGGUCCGAGGCACAGCCCCGCCAAGAGGCCACAACUGUCAGCUGCUUCCGCGGGAAGGGUGAGGGCUACCGGGGCACAGCCAAUACCACCACUGCGGGCGUACCUUGCCAGCGUUGGGACGCGCAAAUCCCGCAUCAGCACCGAUUUACGCCAGAAAAAUACGCGUGCAAAGACCUUCGGGAGAACUUCUGCCGGAACCCCGACGGCUCAGAGGCGCCCUGGUGCUUCACACUGCGGCCCGGCAUGCGCGCGGCCUUUUGCUACCAGAUCCGGCGUUGUACAGACGACGUGCGGCCCCAGGACUGCUACCACGGCGCAGGGGAGCAGUACCGCGGCACGGUCAGCAAGACCCGCAAGGGUGUCCAGUGCCAGCGCUGGUCCGCUGAGACGCCGCACAAGCCGCAGUUCACGUUUACCUCCGAACCGCAUGCACAACUGGAGGAGAACUUCUGCCGGAACCCAGAUGGGGAUAGCCAUGGGCCCUGGUGCUACACGAUGGACCCAAGGACCCCAUUCGACUACUGUGCCCUGCGACGCUGCGCUGAUGACCAGCCGCCAUCAAUCCUGGACCCCCCAGACCAGGUGCAGUUUGAGAAGUGUGGCAAGAGGGUGGAUCGGCUGGAUCAGCGGCGUUCCAAGCUGCGCGUGGUUGGGGGCCAUCCGGGCAACUCACCCUGGACAGUCAGCUUGCGGAAUCGGUGAGGCACAACUGCCUGUCUCCCACAGAGAGGAGCUGAGGCAGGGCCAGCAUUUCUGCGGGGGGUCUCUAGUGAAGGAGCAGUGGAUACUGACUGCCCGGCAGUGCUUCUCCUCCUGCCAUAUGCCUCUCACGGGCUAUGAGGUAUGGUUGGGCACCCUGUUCCAGAACCCACAGCAUGGAGAGCCAAGCCUACAGCGGGUCCCAGUAGCCAAGAUGGUGUGUGGGCCCUCAGGCUCCCAGCUUGUCCUGCUCAAGCUGGAGAGAUCUGUGACCCUGAACCAGCGUGUGGCCCUGAUCUGCCUGCCCCCUGAAUGGUAUGUGGUGCCUCCAGGGACCAAGUGUGAGAUUGCAGGCUGGGGUGAGACCAAAGGUACGGGUAAUGACACAGUCCUAAAUGUGGCCUUGCUGAAUGUCAUCUCCAACCAGGAGUGUAACAUCAAGCACCGAGGACGUGUGCGGGAGAGUGAGAUGUGCACUGAGGGACUGUUGGCCCCUGUGGGGGCCUGUGAGGGUGACUACGGGGGCCCACUUGCCUGCUUUACCCACAACUGCUGGGUCCUGGAAGGAAUUAUAAUCCCCAACCGAGUAUGCGCAAGGUCCCGCUGGCCAGCUGUCUUCACGCGUGUCUCUGUGUUUGUGGACUGGAUUCACAAGGUCAUGAGACUGGGUUAGGCCCAGCCUUGAUGCCAUAUGCCUUGGGGAGGACAAAACUUCUUGUCAGACAUAAAGCCAUGUUUCCUCUUUAUGCCUGUA